GAAUCGCUCCCAGCCUGGGAAGAAGCCUCCCACGCCAGGGCCCCGGACCCAGGAGAGGCCAUGGAAAGCCUGAACCCCAGCUGGCUGACACCCCCCACACCCCCAAGGGCCCUUAGUCUGAGACCAACUCUCCUGGACACCAGGGGCCCACGCAGGCCCUCCGUGCCCCAGUUACCUGUGCCCUGGAGGCAGCCACGGAGUCACGACCACGCGGGGGACGCCAGCCCACAGGCGGAGGCCGGUUUCGAGGCGGCUGGCAGCCGCCCCCCCACCCCAUGCCCUUUGGGUGGCACCUGUGCUGGUGGAGUGGGGGUGGCUGGCUUUGCACACAGGCCUGCUCCUGUACCGUGCUGCGACAGCCAUGAAGGAAGAACCUGGCUGAGUCUCCACCUGCCGUGGACUGUACCAGGUUUGGGGAGGCCAGGCACUGCUAAGGGUCAGUCUGCCCAGACCAGUGUGGACACACCAAGUGCCUGCGAGCCCCUGGGAGCUGCCCGUGCCAGGCUGGAGUGCCGGGGAGGGGCGAGGACAGCUGCAGCCCCGAGAUGUAAACAGGCUUGCAGGUAUAAAAGCUGGAGCCCCUGGGCCUCUCCACACCCCAGCCUGACCCACCUUCCAGAACUCUCGAAAGAAGCCAGGCAGAGCAGGAUCCAGCACCACGCGGCGUCUACGUCUGCUCUGGCCCAAGCAGCACCCCCAAUCCGUGCGUGCACCCCACGAAUUGACUCCCUAUCCACCCAGGACCAGGAUGGAGGAGGACUUCUCCUCCCAGAUGAAGAAGAUGGCCUUGGCCAUGGGCACGUCCCUAUCAGACAAGGACAUUGAGCUGCUGCCCACAGACAUGAGACACCACGGGUCCUUCAACUACCUCAAGUUCUUCAAGCACAUCCGCAAGCUCCACGCCUCGGGCCAGCUGGACGACGCCAUCCACACGGCCUUCCAGUCCCUGGACAAGGACAAGAGUGGCUUCAUUGAGUGGAACGAGAUCAAGUACAUCCUGUCCAUCAUCCCCAGCAGCGGGCCCACCACCCCGCUGACAGACGAGGAGGCCGAGGCCAUGAUCCAGGCGGCAGACACACACGGGGACGGGAGGAUCAACUACGAAGAAUUUUCUGAAUUGAUCAAAAAGGAGAAAAUUCCAAAGAAGAAGUAGCACCAUGACUAGCCCUGGCCAGCCAAGGGGCUCCCAUGGGGUAACCGGGGUGACCACGCACCUGGGCAGAAGCCGUUGGGGCCGGUAAGAGGCGGCAGCCGUGAGGGUGGACCCAGCUUUUGAAGGAAAAUGGAAGAAAAGCAGCAUUAAGUGAA